ACUAUCUCCCGGGUGAACGGAGCUUUCGCAGCUGGAGAAGUCUGUCAUCUGGAUCGAGGCCAUCAGAUAACCUGAGUGUCACUCCUCCUGGAUGGUACUUACAUGUCCUUUGCCAAGAGGAGCAGCCAGAAUAAAAUCACCAGUUCCUAGGCUCUUAGGCUCCACCCGGCCCUGAACAGCUGGCUUGUCUUGGAGUCUCUUGUGCCACCCUCCCCAGGAACAGUGGCUUCCUUGUAUUGGCGCCAGCGAUGAUGGGCCAGCUCUGUGCUAAGCUGGAGUGCAAUGGUGCGAUCUCGGCUCACUGCAGUCUCCGCCUCUUGGGUUCAGGCUCAUCCACCUGCAGACAUGGGGCGCAGAAAGUCAAAACGAAAGCCGCCUCCCAAGAAGAAGAUGACAGGCACCCUCGAGACCCAGUUCACCUGCCCCUUCUGCAACCACGAGAAAUCCUGUGAUGUGAAAAUGGACCGUGCCCGCAACACCGGAGUCAUCUCUUGUACCGUGUGCCUAGAGGAAUUCCAGACGCCCAUAACGUAUCUGUCAGAACCCGUGGAUGUGUACAGUGAUUGGAUAGACGCCUGCGAGGCGGCCAAUCAGUAGCGACACAGAGGACCCGCCCCCUGAGCAGCCCCGCGUACUGUGGAUCCAGCUGUUCGGUUCUGGUCCAGAGACAUUCCAGGGGUCCAGGGUGUGGGUCCUGGGCUGUCACAGCCGUGUGUGUGUGUGUGUGUGUGUGUGUGUGUGUGUGUGUGUGUGUGUGUGUAGUGGGUGUGCGUGUGGGUGUGGGUGUGAGUGAGUGUGGGUGUGUGUGGCUGCACGUGUCACUGGGGUGGCCGUGAGUGUGUGCUCACAGGUACGCGGUGGUGUCGGGUUCCUGGGCCUGAGGGGCCUGAACUGAUCUCACUUGGCUCCGAAAGCCUUUGCUGUGUUCCCUGCAGCCCCUGGCCCCCCAGCCUUGGGGCUCUGGCUCCCCCCGGCGGAAUUGGGGGACUGUUUCCUGACAUCCUGGACAAGGGAAGCCCACUAGAGGCUGGAACAGGACCUCUCCAGCCUCCUCACCAGCACCGUGCCCAUCUCAACUGGACUUCCCGCUCUCCUUCUCCACCUUCUAGUGCCCGUGGCCGGGGAUUCAAAGCCGCCGUUCCCCAGGUCCCUGGGCUGGGCCCUGACAGGGAGCCGCCCCCCUCCCCAUGGUAACCAGGAAGCCCGUUUCAUGUUCAGUUGCUUUUGUAGAGGAAGCAAGGGCUGGGAUGGGGACAGCUGUCAAUCACAAGCCCUUAAAUAAAGCAGCCAGCGCACA